AGACUGAGGCUCGCUGUGUCCCUGGCUGGAGUGCAGUGGUGCGAUCUUGGCUCACUGUAACCUCUGCCUCCUGGGUUCAAGCGAUUCUCCUUCCUCAGCCUCCCAGGUAGCUGAGAUUACAGGCACAUGCCAGCAUGCCCCACUAAUUUUGUAUUUUUAGUAGAGACAGGGUUUCACCAUGUUGGCCAGGCUGGUCUCGGACUCCUGACUCCAGGCGAUCCACUGCCUCAGCCUCCCAAAGUAACUCCCAUUUUUUAAGCCAUCAGAUCUUGUGAGAGUUAUUGCUUAUCAUGAGAACACCACAGGAAAGACCUGCCUCCAUGAUUCAGUUAUCUCCCGCUGGGUCCCUCCCACAACACGUGGGAAUUAUGGGAGCCACAAGAUGAGAUUUGGGUGGGAACACAGAGCCAAACCAUAUCAGGGAGUCACACAGAUAUUUUGAUUUUCCAGUGCAGAUAAAAAUUACAUUUGUACCACCCUAUAGGCUAUUCAGUAUACAGUAGCAUUAUAUCUAAACAACAAUGUACAUACCUUAAGUAAAAAAAAACACUUUAUUGCAAAAAGUCUUAACAAUCAUCUAAGCCUUUAGCAAGUAGUAACCUUUUUGCUGUUAGAGGGUUUUGCCUCAAUGUUAAUGGCUGCUGACUGUUCAAAGUGGUGGUUGCAGAAAUUUGGGGCGGCUGUGGCAGUUUCCUAAACGAAGACAACAAUGAAGUUUGCUGCAUCAAUUGACUCUUCUUUUCACAAAACAUUUCUCUGUAGCAUGUCAUGCCAUUUUACAACAUUUCACCUAUAGUAAAACUUUUUUCAAAAUUGGAAUCAACACUCUCAAUACCUGUUGUUGCUUUAUCAACUAACUUUAUGUAAUACUCAAAUCCUGUGUUGUCAUUUUAACAGUAUAACAGAACACCUCCAUCAGGAGCAGAUUCCAUCUCCAGAAAUCACUUUCUUUGCUCAUCCAUAAAAACAACUCCUCACAACUCCUCAUCCAUUCAGGUUUUAUUAUAAUUUUGCAGCAAUUCACUUACGUCUUCAGGCUCCACUUCUAAAUUUCUUUCUCUUGCUAUUUUCACAUCUCUUUUUAUUUCCACCACAUCUUCCACUGCACUGUUGAACCCCUCAGUGUCAUCCAUGAGAGUGGAAACAACUUUUGAGAUCCAUCUGAGGAAUCACUAUCUCUGGACAGCUAUACCCUAAAUAAAUGGAUUCCUUAAAUAAUAAGACUUGAAACUUCAAAUUACUUCUUGAUUCAUGGGCUUCAGAAUGGUUGUUGUGUUAGCAGGCAUGAAAACAGCAUUAAUAUCCUUGUACAUCUGCAUCAGAACUUUUGGGUGACCAGGUGCGUUAUCAAUGAGCAGUAAUAUUUUGAAAGGAAUCUUUUUUUCUUUCUGAGUAGUGGGUUUAAAAUCUUCAGUAAACCAUGCUGUAAAAAUAGAUAUACUGUCACCCAGGCUUUGUUGUUCUAUUUCUAGAACACAAGCAGAGAUUUAACAUAAUUCUUAAAGGAUCUAGUAUUUUCAGAAAGGUAAAUGAGCAUUGAUUUUAACUUCAAUUCACCAAUGGUGUUAGUCCCUAACAAGAGAGUCUACUUGUCCAAUGGUUCUUUGAAGCUAGCCUUUGACUUUUCCUCACUAGCUAUGAAAGUUCUAGAUGACACCUUCUUCCAACUGAAGACUGUUUCACCUACAUCGACGAUCCGUUGUUUAGUGUAGCCACCUUCAUCUGUCAGCUUAGCUUAUCUUCUGGAUAGCUUGCCACAGCUUCACUUUGUCCUUUUUUGUUAUGGAGACAGCUUCUUUUCUUGAACCUCAUGAACCAACGUCUGCUGGCUUCCAGCUUUUCUGCAGCUUACUCACCUCUCUCACCCUUCAUAGAAUUGAAAAAAGGGCUUUCUGUGGAUUAGAUUUUGGCUUAAGAGAAUGUUGUGGUUGGUCUGAUUUUCUGUUCAGAGAACAAAAACUUUAUUUAGCUCAGCAACAGAAAGUUGUAUCCUUGAAAGUCACCCUGGUAAUUAAUAUAUGAUCAGAAAAGUAAUUGACAAUUUUACUUUGUAGGUUCCUGGGGGCUUUGAAAGAACUAUGUUUAUUUCAGGAAAGGAACAAUAGUAUGUUAUCAUUUGAAAUGAAAACAGUAAAAAUCUGCACUUUCUAUUUAGUAGCCAGAAAAUGUCCAUAAAUCCUGUUUUAGGGCACUGGAAUUUGGAGUAAAUGACCCAUUGUUUGUAUAAAGAUUUAAACAAAGACUGAUCAUCAGCUUUAUUCUUUAUUAUUAAUGUCCUGUGCUUGUUAGUAAAACCCAGUUGCUUGGGUUUUUGUAUCCCUGGAGAGUUUAUUUUUGUUAUCUUUUUCACUGUUAGGCUUCUUACUAAAGAGGGAUUCAAGUAAGUAAAUAACUUAAGAGAAGCAACAGGAAUUGAAAUCUAUAAAGCUUUGUUUUCUCAACUUGGCACAACUGCAUCUGCCUUUGCAGUCUGGGAUUGGAUGAUUGAUUUUAUAUCUUGGAAGCUCAUUUUUAUAUGAGUGUGAAACGAGUCUUUCAAAAUACACUUUGUGAAGAUAACAUUAAUUAGUUACUGUCAUCAACCAACAGGGACAAACCUCUCCUUUUUGUGAUUUCUACAGGAGGAUUGAUUUAACUGUUAAAUUUUGUCAUGUUUUUCAAAGAGCAAUAAAGAAUCCCCCAGGAGGAAGAAUGAGAAAAGAAGCAGCUCAUUUUUGAGGAUAUGCUAUGUACAAAACACCUCAUAAGACAACUGACAGUACCUACCUUUCAGACAAAUUAUCUGAGUCACAGAGAAGUUACAUAAAUUAGUCGUGAUCCCAUAGCAAAUGGUUGAGAAGAUUUAAAGUCAAACAUGUUUCCAUUAUUUAGGACCUAUAAAGUGUCAAGCAUCAUGGUAGUCUUUGGACACAUAAAGUCAACACAGGGCUACUUGGUAGGAGUUACUUCUAGGUAAAAGUCAUUGUUCUCUAAAACUCUAGCCCUGUUAGUGUAUUACAGAAUGCUAUUGGAAAUGGAGCUUAUAGACUAUAUGAAGAAUCUGUAACAGAGGACAUGGAAGCAGAGAAGUUUUUUUAAUGUUAGACCAAUGAUUUGUAUUACAUCUGAAAUGCUCCAAAAUCUGAAACUUUUUGAGUGUCAACAUGAAGCUCAAAGGAAAUUCUCAUUGGAGUAUAUUGCAUUUUGCAUUUUCUGAUUAGGAAUGCUCAACCGGUAAGUAUAUAUAAUGCAAAUAUUACAAAAUCUUAAAAAAUUCAAAAUCUAAAAUACUUCUGGUCACAACCAUUUUGGAUAAGGGCCACUCAGCCUGUAUCACUGUCAGUUCUGUACUGGGAAGCCAUAUGUGUUUUUGAACAAAGGAAUUAUGUUAUUUAGAUUGACUUUGUUAAUUGUAAUUUUUAAUAAAAAUUUACAAUUUUCUGGUGAAUUUUAUCUCUAGUAAAAUUUAGUCUGUGAUAUUUUGCUUACAUUCUACUUUGCUAAACCAUUUCCUUAUUCCUAAGCACGGAAUGAUUGGAUCUGGUGACUGGACUUCACUGCUCCUUGCUCUCACCCUCCUCAGCAAAUUUCAGUUUUACCUCCUCUCCUCUCACAGUUUUAAUUCCUAGGUCUAAAUUACAGAUAGCCAUCUGCCUACCCCCAACUCAUGCACCUAUUUACUAAUUUCCCAAAUAUUUUUAAGCGCUUUCUAUGUGCCAGGCCUUGAGUGCACAAAUAUUCGUUAAGUGCUUUCCAUGUGCCAUGCCUUGGGGCAUGGUGGUAAGUAAGGCAAACCUAGUCCUAUACCUCGGGAACUUACCUUCUAAUUGAGGAGGCAAACAAGAAACAGCAAUUAGUCUAAUUGCUUUAUUAUAUGUGCUAUGAGAGACAAGGAUAACAUGUUAGGAGAGCAUAUUAGAAAAGGGGUGAGAAUAGGGAAUUAUCCUAGCAGGGUAGAUCAGGGAGAUGACAUUUGUGCUGAGACCUAAAGAGUGAAUAGAGUUAACCAAGCAAAAAAAUGUGGGAUGCAGGUUGCCGGGGAGAGGUUGGGUGUCAGCUGGGGUCACCAAAGGGAUGAACUCAGAAGAGGAAGUAUAUUUUAUUUUAUUUCCCAUCUGAAUUUUCUAGCACCAUAGUGUCUGCACAUUUAGAUUUUAUUAAAUAAAAAUGUAAAGUAGUAUAUUUUGCUUCACUUCCUGAUUGCACAUUCCUAGAAUAUUGGAAUUUAUAUUUUAACUACCACAGUGCCUCGAAUAAUCCUUUGCAUAUAAUAUUUUCUCUACUGGUACUUGAUUUAAUAUACUAACAUUUUUUGCUUGAUUUGGAAUGGAGUCGGUAAAGAAGAAAGAAUUUUUUUAUAAAAAUAACUUACAUAGUCAUUACUUACCCUAUUAUAAUUUCACGAUUGACUUACAAUUAUUUAGUUAUGGUCAUUUGAAUGUGCUACUUAAAAUUUGUCAUGAGUAAUUUUUAGAUUAAAGAAGAGCAAUGUUGAAAAUGAAACUACUUGUGUAUUUAGAAAGGUGAUUACAAUUGACAGUAUUUUAUUGUACAUUUUAAAAUAACUAAGAGUAAAAUUGGAUUAUUUCCGUAACACUGAGAAAGGAUAAAUGCUUCAGGUCAUGGAAACCCCAUUUUCUCUAUUAUAUAUAAUAAUGUGAUUAUUAAGCAUUGUAUGCCUGUAUCAACAUAUCUCAUGUACCUCAUAAAUAUAUACACUUAUUAUGUACCCACAAAAUUAAAAAUUAAAAAAAGAAAAAGGAAAACAGAAAGGUGUGUAGAAGCUAUAUCAUUUAGUGGUGUUGAAAGUUUUAAUUUGAGAUGUUUAGAUAAAUGGACCACUCUUUUUCAGGUUGUAUUGUUUUUGACUGUUGAAAAGCAGAAUGCAGAUACAUUCAUUUUAUUAAUUGUAGAGCUCUUAUACUUUUGAAAGAGAGCAAGUUAUUGUGCUUUAGAAUUGUACUGACUUUUUUUUGUUUUGAUGGUGUCUUAACGAAUAAAAAUAAUCUUAUUAACAACAAUAAAAAUUCCUAGAUUUCGUAGCUUUAAUAAAGAUAACACUUAUCUCACCAGGUAAUAUGAAAAAUAACAUACAGUUUUAAGAUUCCAAGGUUCUCACCAGAAGCUCUAUAUUAUGAAGAAGAGACUGCUGUUAUAAUUUUGUGUAUAAAGAAGAAUCAAGCAGGGAAAUUAAGGAGAAAUCCAAGUAACCAAGACCUUUAACAGUGUACACAAUGACUGAACUUUUUAUAGGCUUUCUCAAACUUUUUCAUUUUCAUGCGAUAUAUAAACCCUGCCCCUGCAGUCAUGUGUAUUUCCCUAUGACUUAAUUUUCUCAUCUGUCAAAUGGGGUACUAAAUAGUACCUGUUUCAGAGUGUAUUGGAAGAUUAAGUAAUUUGAAGUUUAGAAGAUGUCUAAUACUCAGUGAGUACACAAUUAAUAUUAGCUGUUGUUUGCUCAAUAGUCCAAAUGAUCAAGUAACUUUUUUCAAUAAGGAAACACAUCUUUUUGAACCUUUCGUAAACAAGUUCUUUAGUUGUUUUUACAUAACUAAACAAAUACUUAUUUGGGUUAAUUUGGUUUCUUUAAGGAGAACCUUGAAGAACUUUUCCCCAACAUUUUAUAAUUUAAAAUAUUGUGAGAAAGUGACUAGAAACAGAUACUUUUCCAUUAAGUUUAUAAAGGACAUAGGGAAACUUUAUAUGCACACUCAGGUCAUUGUUUUGUUUUGUUUGUGGUUUUUCAAUACAAGAAAGUAUUUGCUUUUGAUUCUUUUUCUGUUCCAACUCAUGUUUUCUUCCUCGGGAGCAGCUGUCAUUCUUAGGUAGAAUCUCCUUUCUUUGUGUACUCUAUUAACUUCUCUUCCAUCUCAGAGUAAUUGAUUCCUCAGCAUUUUAUUGAUGAUAUGGAACAGCUUUUGAAAUAAUUUCUUCAGUUUUCUGUGCGAAAUCACUUUUUUUCCCCCCAACAGGGUUUUGCUCUGUCACCCAGGCUGGAAUGCAGUGGUACAACCUAGGCUCACUGCAGCCUCUGCCUCCCAGGUUCAGAUUACAGGCGUGCAGCACCACACCUGACUAAUUUUUGUAUUUUUAUUAGAGAUGGGGUUUCACCAUGUUGGCCAGUCUGUUCUCAAACUCCUGACCUCAAGUGAUCUGCCCACCUCAGCCUCCCAAAGUGCUGGGAUUACAGGCGUGAGCCACUGCGCCCGGCCUUAAAUCACUUUUGAGGUAGAUGUUUUUCUUUCCGAUAUGUCGGGACAAAAUUACCUUUUCUUGUGCUGCAGCAUUUUUUUCAUAGUCUUCAUAUAUUUAUUUUACUAUUUACCUUGCUUGAAUGAAGAGACAUCUGGUGAGACUAGGUUUUUACUGGCAGAUAAGAUGUGUGGACUUUCUUCUAAUGGCUCAACUUCCACAUGAGUGAUGGUCAUAUUCCCUUUCCAUCUCUGUAACUAGAAGGAAGGUUGAUAAGCUUAGAUUCAGCCCAGUUCUCAGUGGCUAGCAUCAUAUGAAAUGAAGUCAGGGUGUCUUUUAUCUCUGUUGCCUCUGAUUGUUAUUGUGUUCCAUAUGGUGACAUCAUAGACAUCUACAAAUUCCACCAUAUGCAGUUACCAGGAUCAUCCCUGAAUACACCCUGUUGAUAACAGUUAACUUGCGGGUGUACCUCCUGCACUGCAGGCUUAACAGCUGCCAUCUCUGUUUCUUUCUUCUUUCACUCAUCAAUUAUUUUUGCUUUUUUUCCCUGUUAAUUGCAAUAUCUGAAUGGCCAUACACAUAGGAGGUUGUGAAUAGUACUCUGGCCAUUUAAAAAUAAUGUUUAAAAUAGGGAAAUAGGCCAGAUCUGGUAGCUUGUGCUUGUAAUCCCAGCACUUUGGGAGGCCAGAGUGGGCACAUUGCUUGAGCUCAGGAGUUAGAGACAAGCCUGGACACCAUGGCAAAAACCCUUCUCUACAAAAAAAUACAAAAAUUAGCUGGGCAUCAUGAGGUGAACCUGUAGUCCUAGCUACUCAAGAGGCUGAGGUGGGAGGAUGGUGUGAGCCCCAUAGGUAGAGGUUGCAGUGAGCUGAGAUUGCGCCACUGCACACGAACCUAGGCAACAUACUGAGACCCUGUAUUUAAAAAAAAAAAAUUAAAAAAAGAGAAAAUGUAUUUAGUCUUUUAUAAAUGCAGUGUUUUUGGCUAAGAGGCAAUUCAAGGGAAGAUGUUAAACAUCUUCUUUCCUUUUUCUCAAGUGUGUUGGCUUUUUUGUUUCUUGAGCUAAAUCAUAGGCAGGCUACUGAUUCAUUUUUUAUUUCAAUUUCAUUGACUUUGUUAUUUGUAGAAAUUCUUGGCAAAGCAUAUAAGGACUGUUUUGCUAGUAAUAGGUUUCAGUUAUAUUUGAGUUUUCAUCGUUUUUAGGGACUAUCUUAGAAAUCACUUUAUACUUAAGCCUCUCAAAGGAGAGGCUUAAGUUGGAGUGCUCAAAACUAGCUAUUUAAUAAAUGGUUAGACUAUUCAAAUAAAUAUUACAGAGCUGAUGAUCUAUAAUAUUUUUCCUUCUUAAUUCUAUGAAAAAGGUAAUUUUAUGGUGUCUAUUAAUUUUUUCCUUUUGUAUUAUGGUUAAGACAAUUUAUUAACUGUAUAAUACACAGCUAUAUGUUAUCAUCUGUGACAUUUUGUGAACAUCCCAUAAGUUAAUGUCACGUAUCAGAGAUAAUGUUCAAAGCUGUUUAUUUUCUAGAAAAUACUUUAUGUCUAGUAUUUGACCAUGCCACACUGCCAUCAGUAUUGUAAGUCUCCUGAGAACUACUGCUGCACAUGAUGAUAUAUGCAUAUGACACAAUAAACACCAGAUCAUAGUUGUAAUUCAUGGAUGAGGUUGGGCUUUCAGUGUUUUGAGCAGGAAAGACUUGAUAGCUUCAGACAAUUUAGUGAGUAAGGGAACGAUCUUUUGGAGGACUGGGAUGUAGGAACUAUAUCCAAGCAUCUGGACUGGCAUAGAAAAGAGGAGAAAGAACAUUUAAAAGGAGUACAAGAUCCUCAGCAUGAGAGAAUUAUUACUGUGUCUACUAAUGGAAGUAUUCACAGCCCAAGGUUUCCUCAUACUUAUCCAAGAAAUACGGUCUUGGUAUGGAGAUUAGUAGCAGUAGAGGAAAAUGUAUGGAUACAACUUACGUUUGAUGAAAGAUUUGGGCUUGAAGACCCAGAAGAUGACAUAUGCAAGUAUGAUUUUGUAGAAGUUGAGGAACCCAGUGAUGGAACUAUAUUAGGGCGCUGGUGUGGUUCUGGUACUGUACCAGGAAAACAGAUUUCUAAAGGAAAUCAAAUUAGGAUAAGAUUUGUAUCUGAUGAAUAUUUUCCUUCUGAACCAGGGUUCUGCAUCCACUACAACAUUGUCAUGCCACAAUUCACAGAAGCUGUGAGUCCUUCAGUGCUACCCCCUUCAGCUUUGCCACUGGACCUGCUUAAUAAUGCUAUAACUGCCUUUAGUACCUUGGAAGACCUUAUUCGAUAUCUUGAACCAGAGAGAUGGCAGUUGGACUUAGAAGAUCUAUAUAGGCCAACUUGGCAACUUCUUGGCAAGGCUUUUGUUUUUGGAAGAAAAUCCAGAGUGGUGGAUCUGAACCUUCUAACAGAGGAGGUAAGAUUAUACAGCUGCACACCUCGUAACUUCUCAGUGUCCAUAAGGGAAGAACUAAAGAGAACCGAUACCAUUUUCUGGCCAGGUUGUCUCCUGGUUAAACGCUGUGGUGGGAACUGUGCCUGUUGUCUCCACAAUUGCAAUGAAUGUCAAUGUGUCCCAAGCAAAGUUACUAAAAAAUACCACGAGGUCCUUCAGUUGAGACCAAAGACCGGUGUCAGGGGAUUGCACAAAUCACUCACCGACGUGGCCCUGGAGCACCAUGAGGAGUGUGACUGUGUGUGCAGAGGGAGCACAGGAGGAUAGCCGCAUCACCACCAGCAGCUCUUGCCCAGAGCUGUGCAGUGCAGUGGCUGAUUCUAUUAGAGAACGUAUGCGUUAUCUCCAUCCUUAAUCUCAGUUGUUUGCUUCAAGGACCUUUCAUCUUCAGGAUUUACAGUGCAUUCUGAAAGAGGAGACAUCAAACAGAAUUAGGAGUUGUGCAACAGCUCUUUUGAGAGGAGGCCUAAAGGACAGGAGAAAAGGUCUUCAAUCGUGGAAAGAAAAUUAAAUGUUGUAUUAAAUAGAUCACCAGCUAGUUUCAGAGUUACCAUGUACGUAUUCCACUAGCUGGGUUCUGUAUUUCAGUUCUUUCGAUACGGCUUAGGGUAAUGUCAGUACAGGAAAAAAACUGUGCAAGUGAGCACCUGAUUCCGUUGCCUUGCUUAACUCUAAAGCUCCAUGUCCUGGGCCUAAAAUCGUAUAAAAUCUGGAUUUUUUUUUUUUUUUUUGCUCAUAUUCACAUAUGUAAACCAGAACAUUCUAUGUACUACAAACCUGGUUUUUAAAAAGGAACUAUGUUGCUAUGAAUUAAACUUGUGUCGUGCUGAUAGGACAGACUGGAUUUUUCAUAUUUCUUAUUAAAAUUUCUGCCAUUUAGAAGAAGAGAACUACAUUCAUGGUUUGGAAGAGAUAAACCUGAAAAGAAGAGUGGCCUUAUCUUCACUUUAUCGAUAAGUCAGUUUAUUUGUUUCAUUGUGUACAUUUUUAUAUUCUCCUUUUGACAUUAUAACUGUUGGCUUUUCUAAUCUUGUUAAAUAUAUCUAUUUUUACCAAAGGUAUUUAAUAUUCUUUUUUAUGACAACUUAGAUCAACUAUUUUUAGCUUGGUAAAUUUUUCUAAACACAAUUGUUAUAGCCAGAGGAACAAAGAUGAUAUAAAAUAUUGUUGCUCUGACAAAAAUACAUGUAUUUCAUUCUCGUAUGGUGCUAGAGUUAGAUUAAUCUGCAUUUUAAAAAACUGAAUUGGAAUAGAAUUGGUAAGUUGCAAAGACUUUUUGAAAAUAAUUAAAUUAUCAUAUCUUCCAUUCCUGUUAUUGGAGAUGAAAAUAAAAAGCAACUUAUGAAAGUAGACAUUCAGAUCCAGCCAUUACUAACCUAUUCCUUUUUUGGGGAAAUCUGAGCCUAGCUCAGAAAAACAUAAAGCACCUUGAAAAAGACUUGGCAGCUUCCUGAUAAAGCGUGCUGUGCUGUGCAGUAGGAACACAUCCUAUUUAUUGUGAUGUUGUGGUUUUAUUAUCUUAAACUCUGUUCCAUACACUUGUAUAAAUACAUGGAUAUUUUUAUGUACAGAAGUAUGUCUCUUAACCAGUUCACUUAUUGUACUCUGGCAAUUUAAAAGAAAAUCAGUAAAAUAUUUUGCUUGUAAAAUGCUUAAUAUCGUGCCUAGGUUAUGUGGUGACUAUUUGAAUCAAAAAUGUAUUGAAUCAUCAAAUAAAAGAAUGUGGCUAUUUUGGGGAGAAAAUUAUGUGUGUGUGUGCUCAAGAUUUAUUUCUUGGACUCUGAGAAAAUGAAAGAUAAAAUUUUCUGUUAUGAUUUUCAUUUAGCAAAAGCAUAUGUCAAUUCAAAAGACAAAAAAAGGGAAGAUACCUGUGAGCCUUCUCUGCCUCUUGUUUCCAAUGCCUUUGAGCAAUGGUUUUAUUUUUCUUACUGGUCUUAAUACAGAUUUCUGGUAAUUUAAGUUUCACCUGACUUGAAAGUUGUAUGGUUUAUGAAAUGCUUGGUGAUAGGUGGUAUGGUAGUAUGAAACUGGAAAAAAACUUGCAGGUUUCCACUCAUGUCUUCAUUGUCACUGGCAACUACUAAAUGGGGUGAGCAUAAAUUGAUUUGGUGCAUGGAUUAUUGUACAUUGCACACUUCAAGAUAUGGUUCCUCAGUUCCAGACAUAGAUUCCUAUUCAGGGCUGGUAUCUUCAGCAUCCUUUCCUCAGCCUUUCAACUUGGCAGAGAUGUCUAGUGUCCAGGGCCUUCUGUCUUCAGACUGCUCUUCAGGCAAGCACCCUUUUCCUGUGCUUUGACACCUGCAGUUCUGCCCUGCCUCCAACUAUGUGGAAAACAAAGAAACAAAAUGAGCCUAUGUGUUCUGUCUUACUUCCUUACCUUUUCCUGGUUUUGUCCUAUCCAUAUAGAGGCCAACUAGAUAUAUGGAAUAUGCAACGUAGUAAGUAGUUGGCAGUUUACAACUUUCAUUAGUAUAGUAAAGACUACUAAGUCUUAGUAAAUAGCCUGUUUAACUGUGUUUAAUCCAUUGUUUCCCAUCUUUGAACGAAAUAUAUUUUCCCUUUUUUAAUAUUUAUUUUUUGUUUACUUAUAAAAUCUUGACAGCCAGAAGAGAUCAUAAGGGUAGCAGUCCUCAGUUGCCAGUCGGUGAGUGGUUACCAUGUGAGGACUAACCACUUUAUAAUCACUUACUCAUAGAUCGUCCUGUGUAUUUUACUAAACACACACACACACACACACACACAUAAAUAGCACAUGACCCUAAUUUCUGAGAAGUACAGUAAGUAUUGACUGUAUUGACCACACACCGUUUUGUGUAUGAUAUCUGUUUCAAGCCUUUGUCCUUGAGACAUGGGCUGUUUUGCCCAGUGAUGUUUACUAAAAUAAAAGCAAGCCUUAAAUGUCA